ACCCGGCCCGGCUCCCUCCCUGCCCGUCCCCGUCCCCCCACCCGUGCCAGCCCCCAGGAUGGGUGCCCCGAGCGCGUGCCGGACGCUGGUGUUGGCUCUGGCGGCCAUGCUCGUGGUGCCGCAGGCAGAGACCCAGGGCCCUGUGGAGCCGAGCUGGGAGAAUGCAGGGCACACCAUGGAUGGCGGUGCCCCGACGUCCUCGCCCACCCGGCGCGUGAGCUUUGUUCCACCCGUCACUGUCUUCCCCAGCCUGAGCCCCCUGAACCCGGCGCACAAUGGGCGGGUGUGCAGCACCUGGGGUGACUUCCACUACAAGACCUUCGACGGCGACGUCUUCCGCUUCCCUGGCCUUUGCAACUACGUGUUCUCUGAGCACUGCCGCGCCGCCUACGAGGACUUCAACGUCCAGCUACGCCGAGGCCUAGUGGGCUCCAGGCCUGUGGUCACCCGUGUUGUCAUCAAGGCCCAGGGGCUGGUGCUGGAGGCGUCCAACGGCUCCGUCCUCAUCAAUGGGCAGCGGGAGGAGCUGCCUUACAGCCGCACUGGCCUCCUGGUGGAGCAGAGCGGGGACUACAUCAAGGUCAGCAUCCGGCUGGUGCUGACAUUCCUGUGGAACGGAGAGGACAGUGCCCUGCUGGAGCUGGAUCCCAAAUACGCCAACCAGACCUGUGGCCUGUGUGGGGACUUCAACGGCCUCCCGGCCUUCAACGAGUUCUAUGCCCACAACGCCAGGCUGACCCCGCUCCAGUUUGGGAACCUGCAGAAGUUGGAUGGGCCCACGGAGCAGUGCCCGGACCCGCUGCCCUUGCCGGCCGGCAACUGCACGGACGAGGAGGGCAUCUGCCACCGCACCCUGCUGGGGCCGGCCUUUGCGGAGUGCCACGCACUGGUGGACAGCACUGCGUACCUGGCCGCCUGCGCCCAGGACCUGUGCCGCUGCCCCACCUGCCCGUGUGCCACCUUUGUGGAAUACUCACGCCAGUGCGCCCACGCGGGGGGCCAGCCGCGGAACUGGAGGUGCCCUGAGCUCUGCCCCCGGACCUGCCCCCUCAACAUGCAGCACCAGGAGUGUGGCUCACCCUGCACGGACACCUGCUCCAACCCCCAGCGCGCGCAGCUCUGCGAGGACCACUGUGUGGACGGCUGCUUCUGCCCCCCAGGCACGGUGCUGGAUGACAUCACGCACUCUGGCUGCCUGCCCCUCGGGCAGUGCCCCUGCACCCACGGCGGCCGCACCUACAGCCCGGGCACCUCCUUCAACACCACCUGCAGCUCCUGCACCUGCUCCGGGGGGCUAUGGCAGUGCCAGGACCUGCCGUGCCCUGGCACCUGCUCUGUGCAGGGCGGGGCCCACAUCUCCACCUAUGAUGAGAAACUCUACGACCUGCAUGGUGACUGCAGCUACGUUCUGUCCAAGAAAUGUGCCGACAGCAGCUUCACCGUGCUGGCUGAGCUGCGGAAGUGCGGCCUGACGGACAACGAGAACUGCCUGAAAGCGGUGACGCUCAGCCUGGACGGCGGGGACACGGCCAUCCGGGUCCAAGCGGACGGCGGCGUGUUCCUCAACUCCAUCUACACGCAGCUGCCCCUGUCGGCAGCCAACAUCACCCUGUUCACACCCUCGAGCUUCUUCAUCGUGGUGCAGACAGGCCUGGGGCUGCAGCUGCUGGUGCAGCUGGUGCCACUCAUGCAGGUGUUUGUCAGGCUGGACCCCGCCCACCAGGGCCAGAUGUGCGGCCUGUGUGGGAACUUCAACCAGAACCAGGCUGACGACUUCACGGCCCUCAGCGGGGUGGUGGAGGCCACGGGCGCAGCCUUCGCCAACACCUGGAAGGCCCAGGCUGCCUGUGCCAAUGCCAGGAACAGCUUUGAGGACCCCUGCUCCCUCAGUGUGGAGAAUGAGAACUACGCCCGGCACUGGUGCUCGCGCCUGACCGAUCCCAACAGUGCCUUCUCGCGCUGCCACUCCAUCAUCAACCCCAAGCCCUUCCACUCGAACUGCAUGUUUGACACCUGCAACUGUGAGCGGAGCGAGGACUGCCUGUGCGCCGCGCUGUCCUCCUAUGUGCACGCCUGUGCCGCCAAGGGCGUACAGCUCAGCGACUGGAGGGACGGCGUCUGCACCAAGUACAUGCAGAACUGCCCCAAGUCCCAGCGCUACGCCUACGUGGUGGAUGCCUGCCAGCCCACUUGCCGCGGCCUGAGUGAGGCCGACGUCACCUGCAGCGUUUCCUUCGUGCCUGUGGACGGCUGCACCUGCCCCGCGGGCACCUUCCUCAAUGACGCGGGCGCCUGUGUGCCCGCCCAGGAGUGCCCCUGCUACGCUCACGGCACCGUGCUGGCUCCUGGAGAGGUGGUGCACGACGAGGGCGCCGUGUGUUCAUGUACGGGUGGGAAGCUAAGCUGCCUGGGAGCCUCUCUGCAGAAAAGCACAGGGUGUGCAGCCCCCAUGGUGUACCUGGACUGCAGCAACAGCUCGGCGGGCACCCCUGGGGCCGAGUGCCUCCGGAGCUGCCACACGCUGGACGUGGGCUGUUUCAGCACACACUGCGUGUCCGGCUGUGUCUGUCCCCCGGGGCUGGUGUCGGAUGGGAGUGGGGGCUGCAUUGCCGAGGAGGACUGCCCCUGUGUGCACAACGAGGCCACCUACAAGCCUGGAGAGACCAUCAGGGUCGACUGCAACACCUGCACCUGCAGGAACCGGAGGUGGGAGUGCAGCCACCGGCUCUGCCUGGGCACCUGCGUGGCCUACGGGGAUGGCCACUUCAUCACCUUUGAUGGCGAUCGCUACAGCUUUGAAGGCAGCUGCGAGUACAUCUUGGCCCAGGACUACUGUGGGGACAACACCACCCACGGGACCUUCCGCAUCGUCACCGAGAACAUCCCCUGUGGGACCACCGGCACCACCUGCUCCAAGGCCAUCAAGCUCUUCGUGGAGAGCUACGAGCUGAUCCUCCAAGAGGGGACCUUUAAGGCGGUGGCGAGAGGGCCGGGUGGGGACCCACCCUACAAGAUACGCUACAUGGGGAUCUUCCUGGUCAUCGAGACCCACGGGAUGGCCGUGUCCUGGGACCGGAAGACCAGCGUGUUCAUCCGACUGCACCAGGACUACAAGGGCAGGGUCUGCGGCCUGUGCGGGAACUUCGACGACAAUGCCAUCAAUGACUUUGCCACGCGUAGCCGGUCCGUGGUGGGGGACGCACUGGAGUUUGGGAACAGCUGGAAGCUCUCCCCCUCCUGCCCGGACGCCCUGGCACCCAAGGACCCCUGCACGGCCAACCCCUUCCGCAAGUCCUGGGCCCAGAAGCAGUGCAGCAUCCUCCACGGCCCCACCUUCGCCGCCUGCCGCUCCCAGGUUGACUCCACCAAGUACUACGAGGCCUGCGUGAACGACGCGUGUGCCUGCGACUCGGGUGGCGACUGCGAGUGUUUCUGCACGGCUGUGGCUGCCUACGCCCAGGCCUGCCACGACGCGGGCCUGUGUGUGUCCUGGCGGACUCCGGACACCUGCCCCUUGUUCUGUGACUUCUACAACCCACAUGGGGGCUGUGAGUGGCACUACCAGCCCUGCGGGGCACCCUGCCUAAAAACCUGCCGGAACCCCAGUGGGCACUGCCUGGUGGACCUGCCUGGCCUGGAAGGCUGCUACCCGAAGUGCCCACCCAGCCAGCCCUUCUUCAAUGAGGACCAGAUGAAGUGCGUGGCCCAGUGUGGCUGCUACGACAAGGACGGAAACUACUAUGACGUCGGUGCAAGGGUCCCCACAGCGGAGAACUGCCAGAGCUGUAACUGCACACCCAGUGGCAUCCAGUGCGCUCACAGCCUUGAGGCCUGCACCUGCACCUAUGAGGACAGGACCUACAGCUACCAGGACGUCAUCUACAACACCACCGAUGGGCUUGGCGCCUGCUUGAUCGCCAUCUGCGGAAGCAACGGCACCAUCAUCAGGAAGGCUGUGGCAUGUCCUGGAACUCCAGCCACAACGCCAUUCACCUUCACCACCGCCUGGGUCCCCCACUCCACGACAAGCCCGGCCCUCCCGGUCUCCACCGUGUGUGUCCGCGAGGUCUGCCGCUGGUCCAGCUGGUACAAUGGGCACCGCCCAGAGCCCGGCCUGGGAGGCGGAGACUUUGAGACGUUUGAAAACCUGAGGCAGAGAGGGUACCAGGUAUGCCCUGUGCUGGCUGACAUCGAGUGCCGGGCGGCGCAGCUUCCCGACAUGCCGCUGGAGGAGCUGGGCCAGCAGGUGGACUGUGACCGCAUGCGGGGGCUGAUGUGCGCCAACAGCCAACAGAGUCCCCCGCUCUGUCACGACUACGAGCUGCGGGUUCUCUGCUGCGAAUACGUGCCCUGUGGCCCCUCCCCGGCCCCAGGCACCAGCCCUCAGCCCUCCCUCAGUGCCAGCACGGAGCCUGCUGUGCCUACCCCAACCCAGACCACAGCAACCGAAAAGACCACCCUAUGGGUGACCCCGAGCAUCCGGUCGACGGCGGCCCUCACCUCGCAGACUGGGUCCAGCUCAGGCCCCGUGACGGUCACCCCCUCGGCCCCAGGUACCACCACCUGCCAGCCCCGGUGUCAGUGGACAGAGUGGUUUGAUGAGGACUACCCCAAGUCUGAACAACUUGGAGGGGACGUUGAGUCCUACGAUAAGAUCAGGGCCGCUGGAGGGCACUUAUGCCAGCAGCCUAAGGACAUAGAGUGCCAGGCCGAGAGCUUCCCCAACUGGACCCUGGCACAGGUGGGGCAGAAGGUGCACUGUGACGUCCACUUCGGCCUGGUGUGCAGGAACUGGGAGCAGGAGGGCGUCUUCAAGAUGUGCUACAACUACAGGAUCCGGGUCCUCUGCUGCAGUGACGACCACUGCAGGGGACGUGCCACAACCCCGCCACCGACCACAGAGCUGGAGACGGCCACCACCACCACCACCCAGGCCCUGUUCUCAACGCCGCAGCCUACGAGUAGCCCGGGGCUGACCAGGGCUCCCCCGGCCAGCACCACAGCAGUCCCCACCCUCUCAGAAGGACUGACAUCCCCCAGAUACACAAGCACCCUUGGUACAGCCACCACGGGAGGCCCCACGACGCCUGCAGGCUCCACAGAACCCACUGUCCCAGGGGUGGCCACAUCCACCCUUCCAACACGCUCAGCCCUUCCAGGGACGACGGGGAGCUUGGGCACAUGGCGCCCCUCACAGCCACCCACGCUGGCCCCAACAACAAUGGCAACCUCCAGAGCUCGCCCGACAGGCACAGCCAGCACCGCUUCCAAAGAGCCGCUGACCACGAGCCUGGCGCCAACACUCACGAGCGAGCUGUCCACCUCUCAGGCCGAGACCAGCACGCCCAGGACAGAGACGACAAUGAGCCCCUUGACUAACACCACCACCAGCCAGGGCACGACCCGCUGUCAACCGAAGUGUGAGUGGACAGAGUGGUUUGACGUGGACUUCCCAACCUCAGGGGUUGCAGGCGGGGACAUGGAAACUUUUGAAAACAUCAGGGCUGCUGGGGGCAAGAUGUGCUGGGCACCAAAGAGCAUAGAGUGCCGGGCGGAGAACUACCCCGAGGUAAGCAUCGACCAGGUCGGGCAGGUGCUGACCUGCAGCCUGGAGACGGGGCUGACCUGCAAGAACGAAGACCAGACAGGCAGGUUCAACAUGUGCUUCAACUACAACGUGCGUGUGCUUUGCUGUGACGACUACAGCCACUGCCCCAGUACCCCAGCCACCAGCUCCACGGCCACGCCCUCCUCAACUCCGGGGACGACCUGGAUCCUCACAAAGCCGACCACAACAGCCACUACGACUGCGUCCACUGGAUCCACGGCCACCCCGACCUCCACCCUGAGAACAGCUCCCCCUCCCAAAGUGCUGACCACCACGGCCACCACACCCACAGUCACCAGCUCCAAAGCCACUCCCUCCUCCAGUCCAGGGACUGCAACCGCCCUUCCAGCACUGAGAAGCACAGCCACCACACCCACAGCUACCAGCGUUACACCCAUCCCCUCUUCCUCCCUGGGCACCACCUGGACCCGCCUAUCACAGACCACCACACCCACGGCCACCAUGUCCACAGCCACACCCUCCUCCACUCCAGAGACUGCCCACACCUCCACAGUGCUUACCGCCACGGCCACCACAACUGGGGCCACCGGCUCUGUGGCCACCCCCUCCUCCACCCCAGGAACAGCUCACACUACCAAAGUGCCAACUACCACAACCACGGGCUUCACAGCCACCCCCUCCUCCAGCCCAGGGACGGCACUCACGCCUCCAGUGUGGAUCAGCACAACCACCACACCCACAACCAGAGGCUCCACGGUGACCCCCUCCUCCAUCCCGGGGACCACCCACACCGCCACAGUGCUGACCACCACCACCACAACUGUGGCCACUGGUUCUAUGGCAACACCCUCCUCUAGCACACAGACCAGUGGUACUCCCCCAUCACUGACCACCACGGCCACUACGAUCACGGCCACCGGCUCCACCACCAACCCCUCCUCAACUCCUGGGACAACUCCCAUCCCCCCAGUGCUGACCACCACCGCCACCACACCUGCAGCCACCAGCAACACAGUGACUCCCUCCUCUGCCCUAGGGACCACCCACACACCCCCAGUGCCGAACACCAUGGCCACCACACACGGGCGAUCCCUGCCCCCCAGCAGUCCCCACACGGUGCGCACAGCCUGGACUUCGGCCACCUCGGGCAUCUUGGGCACCACCCACAUCACAGAGCCUUCCACGGUGACUUCCCACACCCUAGCAGCAACCACCGGUACCACCCAGCACUCGACUCCAGCCCUUUCCAGCCCUCACCCUAGCAGCAGAACCACCGAGUCACCCCCUUCUCCAGGGACGACCACCCCGGGCCACACCACGGCCACCUCCAGGACCACAGCCACGGCCACACCCAGCAAGACCCGCACCUCGACCCUGCUGCCCAGCAGCCCCACAUCGGCCCCCAUAACCACGGUGGUGACCAUGGGCUGUGAGCCCCAGUGUGCCUGGUCAGAGUGGCUGGACUACAGCUACCCCAUGCCGGGGCCCUCUGGCGGGGACUUUGACACCUACUCCAACAUCCGUGCGGCCGGAGGGGCCGUCUGUGAGCAGCCCCUGGGCCUCGAGUGCCGUGCCCAGGCCCAGCCUGGUGUCCCCCUGCGGGAGUUGGGCCAGGUCGUGGAAUGCAGCCUGGACUUUGGCCUGGUCUGCAGGAACCGUGAGCAGGUGGGGAAGUUCAAGAUGUGCUUCAACUAUGAAAUCCGUGUGUUCUGCUGCAACUACGGCCACUGCCCCAGCACCCCGGCCACCAGCUCUACGGCCAUGCCCUCCUCCACUCCGGGGACGACCUGGAUCCUCACAGAGCUGACCACAACAGCCACUACGACUGAGUCCACUGGAUCCACGGCCACCCCGUCCUCCACCCCAGGGACCACCUGGAUCCUCACAGAGCCGAGCACUACAGCCACCGUGACGGUGCCCACCGGAUCCACGGCCACCGCCUCCUCCACCCAGGCAACUGCUGGCACCCCACAUGUGAGCACCACGGCCACGACACCCACAGUCACCAGCUCCAAAGCCACUCCCUUCUCCAGUCCAGGGACUGCAACCGCCCUUCCAGCACUGAGAAGCACAGCCACCACACCCACAGCUACCAGCUUUACAGCCAUCCCCUCCUCCUCCCUGGGCACCACCUGGACCCGCCUAUCACAGACCACCACACCCACGGCCACCAUGUCCACAGCCACACCCUCCUCCACUCCAGAGACUGUCCACACCUCCACAGUGCUUACCACCACGGCCACCACAACCGGGGCCACCGGCUCUGUGGCCACCCCCUCCUCCACCCCAGGAACAGCUCACACUACCAAAGUGCUGACUACCACAACCACGGGCUUCACAGCCACCCCCUCCUCCAGCCCAGGGACGGCACGCACGCUUCCAGUGUGGAUCAGCACAACCACCACACCCACAACCAGAGGUUCCACGGUGACCCCCUCCUCCAUCCCGGGGACCACCCACACCCCCACAGUGCUGACCACCACCACCACAACUGUGGCCACUGGUUCUAUGGCAACACCCUCCUCUAGCACACAGACCAGUGGUACUCCCCCAUCACUGACCACCACGGCCACUACGAUCACGGCCACCGGCUCCACCACCAACCCCUCCUCAACUCCAGGGACAACACCUAUCCCCCCAGUGCUGACCACCACCGCCACCACACCUGCAGCCACCAGCAGCACAGUGACUCCCUCCUCUGCCCUAGGGACCACCCACACACCCCCAGUGCCGAACACCACGGCCACCACACACGGGCGAUCCCUGUCCCCCAGCAGUCCCCACACGGUGCGCACAGCCUGGACUUCGGCCACCUCAGGCACCUUGGGCACCACCCACAUCACAGAGCCUUCCACGGGGACUUCCCACACCCCAGCAGCAACCACCGGUACCACCCAGCACUCGACUCCAGCCCUGUCCAGCCCUCACCCUAGCAGCAGGACCACCGAGUCACCCCCUUCUCCAGGGACGACCACCCCGGGCCACACCAGGGCCACCUCCAGGACCACGGCCACGGCCACACCCAGCAAGACCCGCACCUCGACCCUGCUGCCCAGCAGCCCCACAUCGGCCCCAAUAACCACGGUGGUGACCAUGGGCUGUGAGCCCCAGUGUGCCUGGUCAGAGUGGCUGGACUACAGCUACCCCAUGCCGGGGCCCUCUGGCGGGGACUUUGACACCUACUCCAACAUCCGUGCGGCCGGAGGGGCCGUCUGUGAGCAGCCCCUGGGCCUCGAGUGCCGUGCCCAGGCCCAGCCUGGUGUCCCCCUGCGGGAGUUGGGCCAGGUCGUGGAAUGCAGCCUGGACUUUGGCCUGGUCUGCAGGAACCGUGAGCAGGUGGGGAAGUUCAAGAUGUGCUUCAACUAUGAAAUCCGUGUGUUCUGCUGCAACUACGGCCACUGCCCCAGCACCCCGGCCACCAGCUCUACGGCCACGCCCUCCUCCACUCCAGGGACGACCUGGAUCCUCACAGAGCAGACCACAGCAGCCACUACGACCGCAACCACUGGAUCCACGGCCAUCCCGUCCUCCACCCCGGGAACAGCUCCCCCUCCCAAAGUGCUGACCAGCACGGCCACCACACCCACAGCCACCAGUUCCAAAGCCACUUCCUCCUCCAGUCCAAGGACUGCAACCACCCUUCCAGUGCUGACAAGCACAGCCACCAAAUCCACAGCUACCAGCUUUACACCCAUCCCCUCCUUCACCCUUGGGACCACCGGGACCCUCCCAGAACAGACCACCACACCCAUGGCCACCAUGUCCACAAUCCACCCCUCCUCCACUCCGGAGACCACCCACACCUCCACAGUGCUGACCACGAAGGCCACCACGACAAGGGCCACCAGUUCCAUGUCCACCCCCUCCUCCACUCCGGGGACGACCUGGAUCCUCACAGAGCUGACCACAGCAGCCACUACAACUGCAGCCACUGGCCCCACGGCCACCCCGUCCUCCACCCCAGGGACCACCUGGAUCCUCACAGAGCCCAGCACUACAGCCACCGUGACGGUGCCCACCGGAUCCACGGCCACCGCCUCCUCCACCCGGGCAACUGCUGGCACCCUCAAAGUGCUGACCAGCACGGCCACCACACCCACAGUCAUCAGCUCCAGAGCCACUCCCUCCUCCAGUCCAGGGACUGCAACCGCCCUUCCAGCACUGAGAAGCACAGCCACCACACCCACAGCUACCAGCGUUACAGCCAUCCCCUCUUCCUCCCUGGGCACCGCCUGGACCCGCCUAUCACAGACCACCACACCCACGGCCACCAUGUCCACAGCCACACCCUCCUCUACUCCAGAGACUGUCCACACCUCCACAGUGCUUACCACCACGACCACCACAACCAGGGCCACCGGCUCUGUGGCCACCCCCUCCUCCACCCCAGGAACAGCUCACACUACCAAAGUGCCGACUACCACAACCACGGGCUUCACAGCCACCCCCUCCUCCAGCCCAGGGACGGCACUCACGCCUCCAGUGUGGAUCAGCACAACCACCACACCCACAACCAGAGGCUCCACGGUGACCCCCUCCUCCAUCCCGGGGACCACCCACACCGCCACAGUGCUGACCACCACCACCACAACUGUGGCCACUGGUUCUAUGGCAACACCCUCCUCUAGCACACAGACCAGUGGUACUCCCCCAUCACUGACCACCACGGCCACUACGAUCACAGCCACCGGCUCCACCACCAACCCCUCCUCAACUCCAGGGACAACUCCCAUCCCCCCAGUGCUGACCACCACCGCCACCACACCUGCAGCCACCAGCAGCACAGUGACUCCCUCCUCUGCCCUAGGGACCACCCACACACCCCCAGUGCCGAACACCACGGCCACCACACACGGGCGGUCCCUGCCCCCCAGCAGUCCCCACACGGUGCGCACAGCCUGGACUUCGGCCACCUCGGGCAUCUUGGGCACCACCCACAUCACAGAGCCUUCCACGGUGACUUCCCACACCCCAGCAGCAACCACCAGUACCACCCAGCACUCGACUCCAGCCCUGUCCAGCCCUCACCCUAGCAGCAGGACCACCGAGUCACCCCCUUCUCCAGGGACGACCACCCCGGGCCACACCAGGGGCACCUCCAGGACCACAGCCACAGCCACACCCAGCAAGACCCGCACCUCGACCCUGCUGCCCAGCAGCCCCACAUCGGCCCCCAUAACCACGGUGGUGACCACGGGCUGUGAGCCCCAGUGUGCCUGGUCAGAGUGGCUGGACUACAGCUACCCCAUGCCGGGGCCCUCUGGCGGGGACUUUGACACCUACUCCAACAUCCGUGCGGCCGGAGGGGCAGUCUGUGAGCAGCCCCUGGGCCUCGAGUGCCGUGCCCAGGCCCAGCCUGGUGUCCCCCUGCGGGAGUUGGGCCAGGUCGUGGAAUGCAGCCUGGACUUUGGCCUGGUCUGCAGGAACCGUGAGCAGGUGGGGAAGUUCAAGAUGUGCUUCAACUAUGAAAUCCGUGUGUUCUGCUGCAACUACGGCCACUGCCCCAGCACCCCGGCCACCAGCUCUACGGCCACGCCCUCCUCAACUCCGGGGACGACCUGGAUCCUCACAAAGCUGACCACAACAGCCACUACGACUGAGUCCACUGGAUCCACGGCCACCCCGUCCUCCACCCCAGGGACCACCUGGAUCCUCACAGAGCCGAGCACUACAGCCACCGUGACGGUGCCCACCGGAUCCACGGCCACCGCCUCCUCCACCCAGGCAACUGCUGGCACCCCACAUGUGAGCACCACGGCCACGACACCCACAGUCACCAGCUCCAAAGCCACUCCCUUCUCCAGUCCAGGGACUGCAACCGCCCUUCCAGCACUGAGAAGCACAGCCACCACACCCACAGCUACCAGCUUUACAGCCAUCCCCUCCUCCUCCCUGGGCACCACCUGGACCCGCCUAUCACAGACCACCACACCCACGGCCACCAUGUCCACAGCCACACCCUCCUCCACUCCAGAGACUGCCCACACCUCCACAGUGCUUACCACCACGGCCACCACAACCAGGGCCACCGGCUCUGUGGCCACCCCCUCUUCCACCCCAGGAACAGCUCACACUACCAAAGUGCCGACUACCACAACCACGGGCUUCACAGUCACCCCCUCCUCCAGCCCAGGGACGGCACGCACGCCUCCAGUGUGGAUCAGCACAACCACCACACCCACAACCAGUGGCUCCACGGUGACCCCCUCCUCCGUCCCGGGGACCACCCACACCCCCACAGUGCUGACCACCACCACCACAACUGUGGCCACUGGUUCUAUGGCAACACCCUCCUCUAGCACACAGACCAGUGGUACUCCCCCAUCACUGAUCACCACGGCCACUACGAUCACGGCCACCGGCUCCACCACCAACCCCUCCUCAACUCCAGGGACAACACCUAUCCCCCCAGUGCUGACCACCACCGCCACCACACCUGCAGCCACCAGCAGCACAGUGACUCCCUCCUCUGCCCUAGGGACCACCCACACACCCCCAGUGCCGAACACCACGGCCACCACACACGGGCGAUCCCUGUCCCCCAGCAGUCCCCACACGGUGCGCACAGCCUGGACUUCGGCCACCUCAGGCACCUUGGGCACCACCCACAUCACAGAGCCUUCCACGGGGACUUCCCACACCCCAGCAGCAACCACCGGUACCACCCAGCACUCGACUCCAGCCCUGUCCAGCCCUCACCCUAGCAGCAGGACCACCGAGUCACCCCCUUCCCCAGGGACGACCACCCCGGGCCACACCACGGCCACCUCCAGGACCACGGCCACGGCCACACCCAGCAAGACCCGCACCUCGACCCUGCUGCCCAGCAGCCCCACAUCGGCCCCCAUAACCACGGUGGUGACCACGGGCUGUGAGCCCCAGUGUGCCUGGUCAGAGUGGCUGGACUACAGCUACCCCAUGCCGGGGCCCUCUGGCGGGGACUUUGACACCUACUCCAACAUCCGUGCGGCCGGAGGGGCCGUCUGUGAGCAGCCCCUGGGCCUCGAGUGCCGUGCCCAGGCCCAGCCUGGUGUCCCCCUGGGGGAGUUGGGCCAGGUCGUGGAAUGCAGCCUGGACUUUGGCCUGGUCUGCAGGAACCGUGAGCAGGUGGGGAAGUUCAAGAUGUGCUUCAACUAUGAAAUCCGUGUGUUCUGCUGCAACUACGGCCACUGCCCCAGCACCCCGGCCACCAGCUCUACGGCCAUGCCCUCCUCCACUCCGGGGACGACCUGGAUCCUCACAGAGCUGACCACAACAGCCACUACGACUGCAUCCACUGGAUCCACGGCCACCCCGUCCUCCACCCCGGGAACAGCUCCCCCUCCCAAAGUGCUGACCAGCCCGGCCACCACACCCACAGCCACCAGUUCCAAAGCCACUUCCUCCUCCAGUCCAAGGACUGCAACCACCCUUCCAGUGCUGACAAGCACAGCCACCAAAUCCACAGCUACCAGCGUUACACCCAUCCCCUCCUCCACCCUUGGGACCACCGGGACCCUCCCAGAACAGACCACCACACCCGUGGCCACCAUGUCCACAAUCCACCCCUCCUCCACUCCGGAGACCACCCACACCUCCACAGUGCUGACCACGAAGGCCACCACGACAAGGGCCACCAGUUCCACGUCCACCCCCUCCUCCACUCCGGGGACGACCUGGAUCCUCACAGAGCUGACCACAGCAGCCACUACAACUGCAGCCACUGGCCCCACGGCCACCCCGUCCUCCACCCCAGGGACCACCUGGAUCCUCACAGAGCUGACCACAACAGCCACUACGACUGCGUCCACUGGAUCCACGGCCACCCCGUCCUCCACCCCAGGGACCACCUGGAUCCUCACAGAGCCGAGCACUACAGCCACCGUGACGGUGCCCACCGGAUCCACGGCCACCGCCUCCUCCACCCAGGCAACUGCUGGCACCCCACAUGUGAGCACCACGGCCACGACACCCACAGUCACCAGCUCCAAAGCCACUCCCUCCUCCAGUCCAGGGACUGCAACUGCCCUUCCAGCACUGAGAAGCACAGCCACCACACCCACAGCUACCAGCUUUACAGCCAUCCCCUCCUCCUCCCUGGGCACCACCUGGACCCGCCUAUCACAGACCACCACACCCACGGCCACCAUGUCCACAGCCACACCCUCCUCCACUCCAGAGACUGUCCACACCUCCACAGUGCUUACCGCCACGGCCACCACAACCGGGGCCACCGGCUCUGUGGCCACCCCCUCCUCCACCCCAGGAACAGCUCACACUACCAAAGUGCCGACUACCACAACCACGGGCUUCACAGCCACCCCCUCCUCCAGCCCAGGGACGGCACUCACGCCUCCAGUGUGGAUCAGCACAACCACCACACCCACAACCACCACACCCACAACCAGUGGCUCCACGGUGACCCCCUCCUCCAUCCCGGGGACCACCCACACCGCCAGAGUGCUGACCACCACCACCACAACUGUGGCCACUGGUUCUAUGGCAACACCCUCCUCUAGCACACAGACCAGUGGUACUCCCCCAUCACUGACCACCACGGCCACUACGAUCACGGCCACCGGCUCCACCACCAACCCCUCCUCAACUCCAGGGACAACACCCAUCACCCCAGUGCUGACCAGCACGGCCACCACACCCGCAGCCACCAGCUCCAAAGCCACUUCCUCCUCCAGUCCAAGGACUGCAACCACCCUUCCAGUGCUGACAAGCACAGCCACAAAAUCCACAGCUACCAGCUUUACACCCAUCCCCUCCUCCACCCUGUGGACCACGUGGACCGUCCCAGCACAGACCACCACACCCAUGUCCACCAUGUCCACAAUCCACACCUCCUCUACUCCAGAGACCACCCACACCUCCACAGUGCUGACCACCACAGCCACCAUGACAAGGGCCACCAAUUCCACGGCCACACCCUCCUCCACUCUGGGGACGACCCGGAUCCUCACUGAGCUGACCACAACAGCCACUACAACUGCAGCCACUGGAUCCACGGCCACCCUGUCCUCCACCCCAGGGACCACCUGGAUCCUCACAGAGCCGAGCACUAUAGCCACCGUGAUGGUGCCCACCGGUUCCACGGCCACCGCCUCCUCCACUCUGGGAACAGCUCACACCCCCAAAGUGGUGACCACCAUGGCCACUAUGCCCACAGCCACUGCCUCCACGGUUCCCAGCUCGUCCACCGUGGGGACCACCCGCACCCCUGCAGUGCUCCCCAGCAGCCUGCCAACCUUCAGCGUGUCCACUGUGUCCUCCUCAGUCCUCACCACCCUGAGACCCACUGGCUUCCCCAGCUCCCACUUCUCUACUCCCUGCUUCUGCAGGGCAUUUGGACAGUUUUUCUCGCCCGGGGAAGUCAUCUACAAUAAGACCGACCGAGCCGGCUGCCAUUUCUACGCAGUGUGCAAUCAGCACUGUGACAUUGACCGCUUCCAGGGCGCCUGUCCCACCUCCCCACCGCCAGUGUCCUCCGCCCCGCUGUCCUCGCCCUCCCCUGCCCCUGGCUGUGACAAUGCCAUCCCUCUCCGGCAGGUGAAUGAGACCUGGACCCUGGAGAACUGCACGGUGGCCAGGUGCGUGGGUGACAACCGUGUCGUCCUGCUGGACCCAAAGCCUGUGGCCAACGUCACCUGCGUGAACAAGCACCUGCCCAUCAAAGUGUCGGACCCGAGCCAGCCCUGUGACUUCCACUAUGAGUGCGAGUGCAUCUGCAGCAUGUGGGGCGGCUCCCACUAUUCCACCUUUGACGGCACCUCUUACACCUUCCGGGGCAACUGCACCUAUGUCCUCAUGAGAGAGAUCCAUGCACGCUUUGGGAAUCUCAGCCUCUACCUGGACAACCACUACUGCACGGCCUCUGCCACUGCCGCUGCCGCCCGCUGCCCCCGCGCCCUCAGCAUCCACUACAAGUCCAUGGAUAUCGUCCUCACUGUCACCAUGGUGCAUGGGAAGGAGGAGGGCCUGAUCCUGUUUGACCAAAUUCCGGUGAGCAGCGGUUUCAGCAAGAACGGCGUGCUUGUGUCUGUGCUGGGGACCACCACCAUGCGUGUGGACAUUCCUGCCCUGGGCGUGAGCGUCACCUUCAAUGGCCAAGUCUUCCAGGCCCGGCUGCCCUACAGCCUCUUCCACAACAACACCGAGGGCCAGUGCGGCACCUGCACCAACAACCAGAGGGACGACUGUCUCCAGCGGGACGGAACCACUGCCGCCAGUUGCAAGGACAUGGCCAAGACGUGGCUGGUCCCCGACAGCAGAAAGGAUGGCUGCUGGGCCCCGACUGGCACACCCCCCACUGCCAGCCCCGCAGCCCCGGUGUCUAGCACACCCACCCCCACCCCAUGCCCACCACAGCCGCUCUGUGAUCUGAUGCUGAGCCAGGUCUUUGCUGAGUGCCACAACCUUGUGCCCCCGGGCCCAUUCUUCAACGCCUGCAUCAGCGACCACUGCAGGGGCCGCCUUGAGGUGCCCUGCCAGAGCCUGGAGGCUUACGCAGAGCUCUGCCGCGCCCGGGGAGUGUGCAGUGACUGGCGAGGUGCAACCGGUGGCCUGUGCGACCUCACCUGCCCACCCACCAAAGUGUACAAGCCAUGCGGCCCCAUACAGCCUGCCACCUGCAACUCUAGGAACCAGAGCCCACAGCUGGAGGGGAUGGCGGAGGGCUGCUUCUGCCCUGAGGACCAGAUCCUCUUCAACGCACACAUGGGCAUCUGCGUGCAGGCCUGCCCCUGCGUGGGACCCGAUGGGUUUCCUAAAUUUCCCGGGGAGCGGUGGGUCAGCAACUGCCAGUCCUGCGUGUGUGACGAGGGUUCAGUGUCGGUGCAGUGCAAGCCCCUGCCCUGUGACGCCCAGGGUCAGCCCCCGCCGUGCAACCGUCCCGGCUUCGUAACCGUGACCAGGCCCCGGGCCGAGAACCCCUGCUGCCCCGAGACGGUGUGCGUGUGCAACACAACCACCUGCCCCCAGAGCCUGCCUGUGUGCCCGCCAGGGCAGGAGUCCAUCUGCACCCAGGAGGAGGGCGACUGCUGUCCCACCUUCCGCUGCAGACCUCAGCUGUGUUCGUACAAUGGCACCUUCUACGGGGUUGGUGCAACCUUCCCAGGCGCCCUUCCCUGCCACAUGUGUACCUGCCUCUCUGGGGACACCCAGGACCCAACGGUGCAAUGUCAGGAGGAUGCCUGCAACAAUACUACCUGUCCCCAGGGCUUUGAGUACAAGAGAGUGGCCGGGCAGUGCUGUGGGGAGUGCGUCCAGACCGCCUGCCUCACGCCCGAUGGCCAGCCAGUCCAGCUGAAUGAAACCUGGGUCAACAGCCAUGUGGACAACUGCACCGUGUACCUCUGUGAGGCUGAGGGUGGAGUCCAUUUGCUGACCCCACAGCCUGCAUCCUGCCCAGAUGUGUCCAGCUGCAGGGGGAGCCUCAGGAAAACCGGCUGCUGCUACUCCUGUGAGGAGGACUCCUGUCAAGUCCGCAUCAACACGACCAUCCUGUGGCACCAGGGCUGCGAGACCGAGGUCAACAUCACCUUCUGCGAGGGCUCCUGCCCCGGAGCGUCCAAGUACUCAGCAGAGGCCCAGGCCAUGCAGCACCAGUGCACCUGCUGCCAGGAGAGGCGGGUCCACGAGGAGACGGUGCCCUUGCACUGUCCUAACGGCUCAGCCAUCCUGCACACCUACACCCACGUGGAUGAGUGUGGCUGCACGCCCUUCUGUGUCCCUGCGCCCAUGGCUCCCCCACACACCCGUGGCUUCCCGGCCCAGGAGGCCACUGCUGUCUGAGAACGUUCUGCCUCCAUCCCCAUGCUCUGUCCACCUGGAGCCAGGAUGUGCAUUGUCUGAUCAUGAAAACCUUGGGCCUCCUCUGCGGAGCCCCCCGGCCUGUGUGUGGCACCCCGCGCUCCGUGCUCCUGCUGCCCACCCCGUGGGUGAAACCGGCCCCAGAAGGGUGAGGGGCCAGCAGGACCCCUUUCGGGAGGGCGCCACUCAGGAGUCCUACCCUGGGAGAGCCUGUGGCCCACCUUGGCCUUGCCCCUCCCUGAUGUCACUGGGACGCCCUGGAACAAACUAAGCAUGUGCGGGCCUAUGUGUCCCUGCCACGGCCGGAGCGCCCGCGCAGCACGGAUUCCAGCUGGCCACGUCCGGCCGCUGGGGCAGACAGGCUGGUCCAGGCAAGGCCAGCUGCUGCCAGGAAGCUGCGACAGGCAAGGCGGCCGCCUGUCCAUGCCUGCUGCAGGGUAACUCAGGGCUGAGGUCGCAACGGCCAGGUCAGAGAGGGGUCAGCAUCCCAAAGCCCCCUCUGCUCAACCCAGCCCAGUUUUGCAAAUAAACCCUGAGCAUUGAGUA